GCCCCAUCGUCACCUUCCUCGCCCAUAGCUAAGGACCCGAGGUAUGAGAAGCGCUGGCUGGACACCUUGUCCGUGCCUCUGUCCAUGGCUCGCAUCUCAAGGUACAAAGCCGGAACGGAAAAAUUAAGGUGGAAUGCGUUCGAGGUGCUCGCCCUGGACGGAGUCAGCUCUGGGAUCCUCCGGUUUUACACAGCCCAGGAUGGCACCGACUGGCUGCGGGCGGUCUCAGCCAACAUCAGGGAGCUGACACUUCAGAACAUGAAGAUGGCGAACAAAUGCUGCUCUCCUUCCGACCAGGUUGUGCAUAUGGGGUGGGUAAAUGAGAAACUCCAAGGAGCUGACUCCUCUCAAACCUUCAGACCCAAGUUCCUAGCACUGAAGGGCCCGUCCUUCUACGUUUUCAGCACUCCUCCGGUGAGCACAUUCGAUUGGGUGCGAGCAGAAAGGACCUAUCACCUCUGUGAGGUGCUAUUUAAAGUUCACAAGUUCUGGCUCACAGAGGACUGCUGGUUGCAAGCAAACUUGUAUCUGGGUCUUCAAGAUUUUGACUUUGAGGACCAGAGGCCCUAUUGCUUCAGCAUCGUGGCCGGCCAUGGGAAGAGCCAUGUUUUCAACGUGGAGCUUGGCAGCGAGCUGGCCAUGUGGGAGAAGUCCUUCCAAAGAGCCACGUUCAUGGAAGUUCAGAGAACCGGG